GAGAAGGAGCCGGGAGGUGAUCCGCAGCGCUGCGACGGGACCGCGCGAUUCCUCUCCCACGCAUCUGGCCCGCGUUCCUGGGCCUCGGCACCGGAUCCCGGCGGGGGUGUGGACCCAGGGCCCACUCUCCCCGGCGCGGCCAGGGCCCCCCAGCGUGCGAGCGCCUAGGGGAUGCCGAGGUUUGGCGGGCGCGGGACCAAUAUGGGCAGGGCCGAGGCGGGAUUCUCCCUCUCGCUGUGCCUAGACCGUACUCCUGCUGCAGUUCCGGCAGAGAGCGCGGGGAGAGCAGCGGCGGGAGCUGCGGCGAGCACGCCGGCCCUGGGCUGCUCAAGAUGAGGAGGUGCGCGGGGCCGGGGCGGAGCAGUCGCGUUCCCCGCGUGUGAGCCCCCACCCAUCCCUGGCGCCAGCGCUUCCCCGACCACUCGGGUUCGGCUAUGCGGGAGCCGUGAGGAGGAGGCUUGCAGUCGUGGACCUGAGACCUCGGGAGGUCAUGCUGUCUUGCUUUUAAGUGGCUUGGGGAAAGUGAAGAAACCCCAAAAUGGAGGACUUUGCUACCAGGACCUACGGCACCAGUGGCCUGGACAACAGACCUCUGUUUGGGGAGACGUCCGCCAAGGAUCGAAUCAUCAAUUUAGUUGUUGGCAGCUUAACAUCCUUAUUGAUUCUAGUAACGCUGAUAAGUGCUUUUGUUUUCCCUCAACUACCUCCAAAACCGUUGAAUAUAUUCUUUGCUGUCUGCAUCUCUUUGAGUAGUAUUACUGCCUGCAUACUUAUCUACUGGUAUCGACAAGGAGACUUAGAACCGAAAUUUAGAAAGCUAAUUUACUAUAUCAUAUUUUCUAUCAUCAUGUUGUGUAUAUGUGCAAACCUGUACUUCCAUGAUGUGGGAAGGUGAGGCUGCCAAGGAGAAGUACUUACCAGGACUCUUCAAAAUGAUACAUUAGGACAGUGAGUAAUUUUUGGAUAAGGUAUGCUGAAGAAUCUCCUGCAGAAGUCUGAUACAUGAUUUUCAUGUUAAUUGUAAAUGUUAAUUCCCUCUUGCAAGGGAGACAUAUCCUAGAUCACUUUGCUUUUUCUUUAAGGAGCUGAUGUUGCACCUAAACAUUCCAACCCUUAAAGCUAAAACAGCACAAAAAAAUUUCACUUUUGAAAUGAAAUUUUUAUAAUUGUAUGGCAAAAGGCUAUGUAAAAACAAAUCUUGCAUCUUAAGACAAAUAUUCUUUUAUUUCUGUUAAACUGAAUAUACAAUUGUUCCCUAGGCAACCAACUUUUGCUUAUAACUACAAUUUAAUUUCACGUUGACAAAACACAGUGAAAAGACAACUUUGUGAAGAUCUAAUUACAAUAAUAAAUAAAAUAAUUUAUACAAGG